AGUCGGAGCUAGAGCUCCAAGGACCCCACGCCUGUGUCUCUGUGACAGAGCUCAAAGGGCCCUGGGCCUUCCCUCCCUGGCUCGGCUGUGCUUGGGAGGGUUCCCCAGUCCAGAAUCCCUAAGGAGCAUGGGGCAGCUGAUCCAUCCCUGGUGUACAAACUGCUGACUGCAGACAGAUGCUGAGCUACCCAAACCAACACCUAGCCUCUCCCUGAAGAUCCUCCCAGGCUGAGAGAGUUCUGGGUGUCCUAGGACCAAGGACACUGGCAGACUUCCAGAAGGGCCCCCAAAGCCCUAACCUGUCCAGCCAGAGCAUGCGUCUCAGCAGAGCUGUCUUCCCAAGCCUUUGAUGACAAACCAAUUUCCCUCGAUGAUGUGCUUCUGAGUGCUCUGCUGAGGAACAAUGGGAAGUCUGCCCAGCAGAAGAAAAUCUCUGCCAAGCCCAAGCUUGAGUUCCUCUGUCCAAGGCCAGGGACCUGUGACCAUGGAAGCAGAGAGAAGCAAGGCCACAGCCGUGGCCCUGGGCAGUUUCCCGGCAGGUGGCCCGGCCGAGCUGUCGCUGAGACUCGGGGAGCCAUUGACCAUCGUCUCUGAGGAUGGAGACUGGUGGACGGUGCUGUCUGAAGUCUCAGGCAGAGAGUAUAACAUCCCCAGCGUCCACGUGGCCAAAGUCUCCCAUGGGUGGCUGUAUGAGGGCCUGAGCAGGGAGAAAGCAGAGGAACUGCUGUUGUUACCUGGGAACCCUGGAGGGGCCUUCCUCAUCCGGGAGAGCCAGACCAGGAGAGGCUCUUACUCUCUGUCAGUCCGCCUCAGCCGCCCUGCAUCCUGGGACCGGAUCAGACACUACAGGAUCCACUGCCUUGACAAUGGCUGGCUGUACAUCUCACCGCGCCUCACCUUCCCCUCACUCCAGGCCCUGGUGGACCAUUACUCUGAGCUGGCGGAUGACAUCUGCUGCCUACUCAAGGAGCCCUGUGUCCUGCAGAGGGCUGGCCCGCUCCCUGGCAAGGAUAUACCCCUACCUGUGACUGUGCAGAGGACACCACUCAACUGGAAAGAGCUGGACAGCUCCCUCCUGUUUUCUGAAGCUGCCACAGGGGAGGAGUCUCUUCUCAGUGAGGGUCUCCGGGAGUCCCUCAGCUUCUACAUCAGCCUGAAUGACGAGGCUGUCUCUUUGGAUGAUGCCUAGGCCCAAAGGAGAGGCCAAAAGGGAAACCAAGGCUGCACACCUAGAACCCCAAUUCAGCCUCCUGGGCACCCCAGAGGCAAGGCUGUGCACUCAGGGAGGGAGGGUGGGACACAGAGGUGCAUCUAGGGUCCCACCUGUACCCUUGCUCUUUCCUCUCUUAGCCCUUAGAAGUCACCUACUUCCUUCCAGUGCCAUGAUCCCACCUGCGACCUCUAGUGCGAGUGCAGAGAAGGUGGGACCAGGGCCAGGGUUCCAAAAAGAGAAUAAGCCUCCUGGGGGGUCUGACCUAGUUAGUUCUUGAGUUUGGGGUUUCCAGUACCAUCUGGAUGCCCUGCCUGUUGAGCCCCAUUCUACAUCCCCACCAUUAACCAGGCCCCACCCACAAGGUAGAAACAACCCCUAGAGUCAACGAGAAAGUCAUUUUCAGAAAAUCUACAAGUCUCGUUGAGACCACCACCAUACCUCAGAAGGUAGGACUGUGGCCUAGAAGGGAAAGGAAAGCUGAGAUGAUGUCUUACCGUAGCAGCAGAUCUUGGAUGGUCCAGGCUCUAUGUGACCUCCAGAGCAAAGAGAAAGACUUCGGACAGUCUAGGUCCUCAAAUGUCCCCCAUUGAGGACAACAGCCCCAGCUCUUUUUCUUUUUUUUGAGACGGAGUCUUGCCCUGUUGCCCAUGCUGGAGUGCAAUGGCACGAUCUCAGCUCACUGCAACCUCCAUCUCCUGGAUUCAAACAAUUCUCCUGCCUCAGCCUCCAGAAUAGCUGGGAUUACAGGCGUACACCACCAUGCCUGGCUAAUUUUUUUGUAUUUUUAGUAGACAUGGGGUUUCACCACAUUGGCCAGGCUGGUGUCGAACUCCUGACCUCAGGUGAUCCACCCACCUUGGCCUCCCAAAGUGCUGGGAUUACAGGUGUGAGCCACGGCACCCAGCCUAGCUCUCAGAUCUCUAUUUCAUUUUGUGGCUUACCAUUCCCUAGCACACUGGCCUUGCCAUCUUGUGGCCGAAUAAAAAAUAACACCUCUUAAGUCUAGCACACUGCAGUGAGGCCAGGCACCUCAGUGCUGGGCAGGGGCAUCAGAAGGUGCUAAGCCCUCUCUCCACAAUGCCAAGACGGAGACCACAGCCUACACCAAAUCCAGCCCUUGAUUUCCCUGCUGCCUCCAUAAACAGAAAGAGGUCUGCUGGAUCCGCUAAGGGAUCAGGGAGAGGAAGAAAGAGGGAUGGGGUGGGAGGCACCCCCUCCAGUGCUCCUACUGGUUCCCAAGCUACAGGUGGGGUGGGAAAGGCUUUAUCAGGUAUCAUCAACAGGUUCUCAAUUAAAGAUUUGAUUUAUUCAAGUAUGUGAAAACAUUCUACAAUGGAAACUCUUAUUAGAUGCUGCAUGUACUGUGCUAUGGACCACGCACAUACAGCCAUGCUGUUUCAGAAGACUUGAAAUGCCAUUGAUAGUUUAAAAACUCUACACCCGAUGGAGAAUCGAGGAAGACAAUUUAAUGUUUCAUCUGAAUCCAGAGGUGCAUCAAAUUAAAUGACAGCUCCACUUGGCAAA